GUAUUAAAUGGCAUUUAGAAUCCAAAAUCUGGUUCCUAGAUAAUGCUCAUUGUUAUUGGACCAUUGCUGCUCCCAGGCCUUCUCAUAGACAUAAUGAGGAAAUGAGGUUCUGACACCCCCAUCACAGGCUCUCCCUACUGUGUGGAUGCCCUCCUUAUCUUGCUUGGGCUUUGGUACCCUAUAGCAGGGUGCUCUUCCAUGACAACUCUUUCUUAACUGUGGUUGGCUUCUGACACACUACACCAGGGCACCCCUCUCUCCUGAUACGGAUGCCUUCCUUGCUAUACUUAGACUAUGAUAUUCCACACCAGUCCACCUCCCUGCCCCAAAUGUGGAUGCUCUUUUCACCCUGCUUGGGCUCUGAUUCUCCUCACUAGACUACUUGUCUCUUCCUCCCCCUCCUGAUGGACUCACCCUGCUUAGGUCUGACCACAGUGUUGGGCUGCCCUCAUCAUCUCUUAACUAGACUUUUUUUUUUUUUUUUGAGAUGGAGUCUUGUUCUGUCGCCCAGGCUGGAGUGCAGUGGUGCAAUCUCGGCUCACUGCAACCUCCGCCUCCUAGGUUCAUGCCAUUCUCCUGCCUCAGCCUCCCGAGUAGCUGGGGCUACAGGCGUCUGCCAUCAUGCCCAGCUAAUUUUUUUCUUUUUUUGUAUUUUUAGUAGCAACGGGGUUUCACCGCGCUAGCCAGGAUGGUCUCGAUCUCCCGACCUUGUGAUCUGCCCGCCUCGGUCUCCCAAAGUGCUGGGAUUACAGGUGUGAGCCACCGCGCCUGGCCUUAACUAGACUAUUAUAACACAAAGCCUCCUAACUGAUCUCCUUGCUUUCAAUCUUCUUAUACCUUUCACAUUUCUGCAAGAGUGAUCAUUCUAAAAUAUAAGUCAAAUCAUGCCACUGCUCUGCUUAAAAACAUUGUAAUAGUUCCCUUUUGCUUAGAGAAUAAAUUUCAAGUUCCUUGGGCUGUCAUUCAAGGAUCUCUAGUAUCUGACCCAAAGGUACCUUUCGUCCUCAUUUCUUAUUAGUUCCUUGGUAUACUGUGCACUCCAACUAUCGCCACUGGCUACUCCUUAGACAUACCCCAGUACAUUUACUCCUCUGGCUUUUUGCCUUUAUCCUCUCCUCUGUCUGGCUUAGCCAACUCUCUUCACUGUCUGAUAAAAUCCCUCAGAGUCCUAGUUCAGAUGUCUGCUAUGGAUGUCAGAGCCUGAAUACAGUGAGGAAGAUAACAAUAAGAGGAAGGAAUUACCUGGUGAAACCUCUCUGACCUCUAUAGUCAUAAACAGUCCCCUUUUUUUCUACUUCUGAUGGAGUAUUUACUUCAUUCUCUCUCUUUUCACAAUCAGCUGUUUACAUAUCUGUUGCCUCUGAUUCAUUGGCUGCUCCUUGAAUGCACUCAACACAGGGCAUUGCAUCUAGUAGACCCUCAGGGAAUGCUGAUGGAACUUGUCAAGGGAAUGAAUUUUGGAUGGUGAAGUUACCACAGCAGUGAAUCUGUUGCUUUCAUUUGAAGUCCAUUCACAGGUCCCACUGAGGUCUGAGAGGCUCUGACUACAAGAAAGGGUUUGGAGUCUGGCAUCCUUGGGUCUAGAUAUCUGCCCUGUGCCAGAGCUCUUUCUGAGAAAAUGAUAUAUUCACACUAUUCUCCUCUUUAGUAAAUUCCAAAUAUGUCUUUAAAAAAAAAUCUACACUGUCAUCCUAAAUAAAAUAAUUCCUAGCUACAGGAAUAUAGGUAUUUAAAGCUGCAAAUAAUAGCAGUGACAUCAUCCUACUAAAAAAGCCUGCCCCAAAUUGUCUGAAGGCCAGCAUUGUGAUAUGUGUCUCCUGACAGCCUAUCCCUGCAGAGACCCUCAGUCUGUCUCUGCAGAGACACUUAGGCUGAAGUGUCAGCAAAGGAGGGUUUUAGACUUUCUCAGUGACUUUACCAGUCUGCACUUUUUGGAGCUGUGUGGGAAGCAUCACAGGCUAGGUUCCUUGUAGCAUGUGGGGGUUUCUAGAGGGGAAGAGAAAGAUAGGAGUCUGUAUUUCUUUAGAUCCCACUACCAACCCCAUUUGCUCCAGCCAUAGCAGCAUCUUGAACUUUUCUUGUUCUGAUCAUUCAUUCUUCCGGGGCUUUGUCCAGGUUUUCUUUUCUACCCUGAGAUUGAACUGUCUGAUUUCAAAGCCUAGGCUCUUUUGUGUUUCAUAAUCAUAGCACCGAAUUUUUUUUUUUUUUUUUUUUAAAGAUUGCUCAUUUUUGCUUUUCCUGUCAGGUUUUCAGUCUCAUUAAAAUAAUUUCUAAAUUGAGAUCAGAAUAUUUUCUAAUAUACAGAUUCAAUUUUUGCCUCCACAGGGGUUGAAUCAAGGUAUACUUACCUACAAGACUAACUCUUAUUUUGAUUUGGCCUGAGACACAGUAGAAUGUUCCCAAUUUAAGAUUAGCACUAUUCCAUCUGCCUGGUGCUAAUUGAAACUGAAGAGGAAGGAAAGCUUUUAUUCUAUAAUUGUUUGGAGAGCAGCAUGGAAAACUCCUUAGAAUGUGAUGAACUUGAUAUUUACUAGGUUUAUAAGUUUUGGCAAGUGUUAAGCUCUCUGUGCCCCGAUUUUCUUACCUGUAAAAUGAGGGUAAUAAAGCCAAUUUUUAAAGGGCUGUUAUUAGGUUAAAUGAUAUGAUUCUUGUAGGGUUGACUCUGGUUUUGACUUUGUCACCAACAGUGGGAGGUGGGAGUCAUCAACCUAAGCAUUGUCCCUGGCUUAGUAUAUGCCAUAAUUUCACACUAAAGCUACGUUUACUUCCAUUAUCUUAUAUAACCUUCAUAUUGUGAUCAGAGAAAAAAAGAUGGUGGUGGUGGUUCCCAUUUGUCAAAUAAGGAAAUUGAUACUCAGAGAAGUUGAGUGGCUUGUCUGAAAACAGAGACCUCUGACUCCUAGUCUGAGACUCCUUUUGUUCUUAACAAGUCUUAGGAGAGGGCCGUGUGGUGUAAAAAAAAAAAAAAAAAAAAAAAGAGGCCUUCAAUUGAAAAGUCAAGAAUGGGCUUGGUGCAGUGGCUCAAGCUUGUAGUCCCAGCACUUUGGGAGGCUGAGGUGGGAAGAUUCCUUGAACCCAGGAGUAUUUUUUCUUUUUCAGAAACAGGGUCUUGCUCUGUCACCCAGGCUAUGUGAUCAUAGCCCACUGUAGCCUUGAACUUGUGGGCUCAAGCGAUCCCCCUGCCUUAGCCUCCCAAGUAGCUAGGAUUAUACGCAGAAGCCACUGCACUAAGAAUAUCUUGAUUUUGUAGUUUUAGCUAGGAUAAUUUGGGAAAGUCAACUCAGUUUCUACCUUAUUUAAACAGAAAUAUGAAUUAUUCUUUUUAACUCACUUUGGCAAAUAAUUGUCGAGCAUUUACUAUGCCUUACACGGUGCUAGGCUUGUCCCUUCUGUCAAGCUGUUUAUAUUUCACUAAGGAUAAGAGAUACAGAUAAUUAGUUUAAGUGAAAAGAGUUAUAACAAAUGUGUAUGUGGCAGAAGAUAAUGGUGGCUGUGGUGGGAGUGGUCCAGGAGGGUGCCACAGAGAUAGCCGUGGGGCUGGGCAUUGCUUCUGAGGAGAAAUCUCAAAGGAGGGUAUGUAAGAAUUAAUUGGAUAAUGGAUAUGAAUGUGCUUUAUUAGUUGCCACAUAAAUGCAGCUUUUUACAACUGUCAAUUCUUACAGAAGGUGCCUCUUUUCUAGAAACCUUGGCUGACCGAGUAGAACACCAUAGUUGGAGUCCAAACUUAAUUAAAGUGAGAAGAAAGAUUUUAGUAGAUUGAGAUUUUAUAUUAAAAAAAAAAAAAGCAAAAGCCUGUGUCUGAAGUUUUUGGAAUCCAGGAGUCCUUAAAAUGGGAUGUGUAUGCCUAUUAAAAUUGUCUUCUACUUUGAUGACACAGUGGACCUCAGCCACUUUUGAGUUUAUAAAGGACUUAUUUAUUAUCACUUAAAAAAAAGCCACUUGUGCUCCUGCAGCAUUUUAGAUAUUUAAAACAGCCUUGCAAACAAGUAUGUAUCCUGGGGAAUAAAAUGAAUCAGGACAAGACAAAGAGAAAUUGGGCGGCUGAGCCAAAGAUAUGUAAUGUUUUUAUUUUUUAUAUUUGUUUGGGUUCAGUAGAUGUAAUUAUUGAGAGCUUUGUAUGUGCUAGGCUUUGUAUGAAGUACUGAGGGAACAGAGAUGAAUGAAGCAUUUCGUAAACAAGGGGACAUAUAGUCUGGCUGGAGAUACAAGACAUCUGUGUAGCUGCUGCUGGUGGUGACAAUGUCAAAUAACGGCCUAGACAUUCAAGACAAACCCCCAGCCCCUCCGAUGAGAAAUACCAGCACUAUGAUUGGAGCCGGCAGCAAAGAUGCUGGAACCCUAAACCAUGGUUCUAAACCUCUGCCUCCAAACCCAGAGGAGAAGAAAAAGAAGGACCGAUUUUACCGAUCCAUUUUACCUGGAGAUAAAACAAAUAAAAAGAAAGAGAAAGAGCGGCCAGAGAUUUCUCUCCCUUCAGAUUUUGAACACACAAUUCAUGUCGGUUUUGAUGCUGUCACAGGGGAGUUUACGGGAAUGCCAGAGCAGUGGGCCCGCUUGCUUCAGACAUCAAAUAUCACUAAGUCGGAGCAGAAGAAAAACCCGCAGGCUGUUCUGGAUGUGUUGGAGUUUUACAACUCGAAGAAGACAUCCAACAGCCAGAAAUACAUGAGCUUUACAGAUAAGUCAGCUGAGGAUUACAAUUCUUCUAAUGCCUUGAAUGUGAAGGCUGUGUCUGAGACUCCUGCAGUGCCACCAGUUUCAGAAGAUGAGGAUGAUGAUGAUGAUGAUGCUACCCCACCACCAGUGAUUGCUCCACGCCCAGAGCACACAAAAUCUGUAUACACACGGUCUGUGAUUGAACCACUUCCUGUCACUCCAACUCGGGACGUGGCUACAUCUCCCAUUUCACCUACUGAAAAUAACACCACUCCACCAGAUGCUUUGACCCGGAAUACUGAGAAGCAGAAGAAGAAGCCUAAAAUGUCUGAUGAGGAGAUCUUGGAGAAAUUACGAAGCAUAGUGAGUGUGGGCGAUCCUAAGAAGAAAUAUACACGGUUUGAGAAGAUUGGACAAGGUGCUUCAGGCACCGUGUACACAGCAAUGGAUGUGGCCACAGGACAGGAGGUGGCCAUUAAGCAGAUGAAUCUUCAGCAGCAGCCCAAGAAAGAGCUGAUUAUUAAUGAGAUCCUGGUCAUGAGGGAAAACAAGAACCCAAACAUUGUGAAUUACUUGGACAGUUACCUCGUGGGAGAUGAGCUGUGGGUUGUUAUGGAAUACUUGGCUGGAGGCUCCUUGACAGAUGUGGUGACAGAAACUUGCAUGGAUGAAGGCCAAAUUGCAGCUGUGUGCCGUGAGUGUCUGCAGGCUCUGGAGUUCUUGCAUUCGAACCAGGUCAUUCACAGAGACAUCAAGAGUGACAAUAUUCUGUUGGGAAUGGAUGGCUCUGUCAAGCUAACUGACUUUGGAUUCUGUGCACAGAUAACCCCAGAGCAGAGCAAACGGAGCACCAUGGUAGGAACCCCAUACUGGAUGGCACCAGAGGUUGUGACACGAAAGGCCUAUGGGCCCAAGGUUGACAUCUGGUCCCUGGGCAUCAUGGCCAUCGAAAUGAUUGAAGGGGAGCCUCCAUACCUCAAUGAAAACCCUCUGAGAGCCUUGUACCUCAUUGCCACCAAUGGGACCCCAGAACUUCAGAACCCAGAGAAGCUGUCAGCUAUCUUCCGGGACUUUCUGAACCGCUGUCUCGAGAUGGAUGUGGAGAAGAGAGGUUCAGCUAAAGAGCUGCUACAGGUGAGAAAACUGAGGUUUCAAGUGUUUAGUAACUUUUCCAUGAUAGCUGCAUCAAUUCCUGAAGAUUGCCAAGCCCCUCUCCAGCCUCACUCCACUGAUUGCUGCAGCUAAGGAGGCAACAAAGAACAAUCACUAAAACCACACUCACCCCAGCCUCAUUGUGCCAAGCCUUCUGUGAGAUAAAUGCACAUUUCAGAAAUUCCAACUCCUGAUGCCCUCUUCUCCUUGCCUUGCUUCUCCCAUUUCCUGAUCUAGCACUCCUCAAGACUUUGAUCCUUGGAAACCGUGUGUCCAGCAUUGAAGAGAACUGCAACUGAAUGACUAAUCAGAUGAUGGCCAUUUCUAAAUAAGGAAUUUCCUCCCAAUUCAUGGAUAUGAGGGUGGUUUAUGAUUAAGGGUUUAUAUAAAUAAAUGUUUCUAGUCUUCCGUGUGUCAAAAUCCUCACCUCCUUCAUAACCAUCUCCCACAAUUAAUUCUUGACUAUAUAAAUUUAUGGUUUGAUAAUAUUAUCAAUUUGUAAUCAAUUGAGAUUUCUUUAGUGCUUGCUUUUCUGUGACUCAACUGCCCAGACACCUCAUUGUACUUGAAAACUGGAACAGCUUGGGAAUGCCAUGGGGUUUGAUAAUCUGCCAGGGACAUGAAGAGGCUCAGCUUCCUGGACCAUGACUUUGGCUCAGCUGAUCCUGACAUGGGAGAACAACCACAUUUUUCUUUGUGUGUGCUUCUAGCAGCUGUUCGGGAGGACCUUGACCCAAUAGUGUUCCCAUGCUGUUUCUUGUGAAAUGCUCUCGGCUAUGUAGCAGCUUUUGAUUCCCUGCAUACCCUAGGCUGCUGCCCCUAUCCUGUCCCUUGUUUAUAACAUUGAGAGGUUUUCUAGGGCACAUACUGAGUGAGAGCAGUGUUGAGAAGUCGGGGAAAAUGGUGACUACUUUUAGAGCAAGGCUGGGCAUCAGCACCUGUCCAGCUCUACUUGUGUGAUGUUUCAGGAACUCAGCCCCUUUUUCUGCCUAGGAUAAGGAGCUGAAAGAUUAACUUGGAUCUUCUAAUGGUCCAAAUCUUUUGGUCACAAUAAAGAGUCUCCAAAUUAGAGACUGCAUGUUAGUUCUGGAUGGAUUUGGUGGCCUGACAUGAUACCCUGCCAGCUGUGAGGGGACCCCGUUUUUAAGAUGCAUGGCCAAGCUCUCUGCAAAUGGAAAUGCUUACACUGGGUGUUGGGGAUGUUUGCUACCUCCUGCUAUUUUUGUGGUUUUGGUUCUCCCACUAUGGUAGGACCCCUGGCCAGCAUUGUGGCUUGUCAUGUCAGCCCCAUUGACUACCUUCUCAUGCUCUGAGGUACUACUGCCUCUGCAGCACAAAUUUCUAUUUCUGUCAAUAAAAGGAGAUGAAAAUAUUC